CUCUUCGUCCCCAGUGGCGAGCAAGUCUGUCGGUGGCUCAUCACAGAGCACUGUUUUGGAAAGCGUUCCACCCACCUCAGCUUCGUGCUGUGUUUGGGCCACUAGUCAGGGGGAAGGAUGCUGAGCGACAUGGACUUUAGAGUCAAAGAAGAUGGCCACGGAGACAGCAGCGUGGUCAGAGUGGUAGGAGCCGGCCAUCAGCGAGAGCUGCUCCAUGCCUGGCUGCUGGGUGCUACAGCCUGUGGCCCACUGGCUUGCCUCACUGUGGUUGGUGGUGGCGGUGACAGAGACUGCAGCACGACCAAAGUGGCUUUUCUGGCUUUGCCCGCCCAGCUGCUCCAUGCCAGGAGGAGGAGGAGACACCUAGAGCCUGCGACACCACGGCUCGCCUCGCUGCGGGAGGGUGGCAUCAACGGAGACUGCAGUGCACCAGAGUGCCCCCACAUCACCCAACCAACCAGCAGAGAUCCUCCUUCCCAAGAAACAGAUAAAGAAACUGAGGCCCAGGAAGGCUAAGAGUCCUGCCAGGAUUAUUCACCUUUCAAGCAGCCAAGCAAGCACUGGCUGUGAGAGA